AUGUUGAGUCCCGGAGCUGCAGCGAGCCGGCGCGCUCCACCCCGGGCCAGCGUCUCGGCGGCCACCCAGGGAACUGCAGCCCGAGGUGUGAGCGGGAGGUACUCCCGGCGCUGGGUACGCUCCGGGCACCUCCACCCCCAGUCUCCACCGAGCGGGCUCUCGGCCUCGCGCCUCUGGCCAGGCCAGGGGCUGCCCAAGGCCAGGCUCUACCUCUCCCUUGCGUUCUUUGUCCCCACUCAGCCCGCUCCCGCUCUCAGCCAGAAGCUGCGCUGGGCACUCGGGAGAAAGCCGGGACAAUUCUGGGGUCCAGUCUUCCCGGACUCCCUCCUCCACGCCAGCGACCGGGUGGCAGCUAUAGGGAACCAGGCUUCGGAAGUCUUGCCAACCAGACAAAACAGACCCGAGGAAGCCCCCCUCCUCCCGCUUUCCGCGAGCCCCGGUUUGCUUUCCGCACCGUUUGCUGGGCGCCAGCAGCCAGACUCUCGGCUGGGAUCUGAAGUGCUGGAGGCACCCUGUCGGGGAGGAGAGAUGCCGCCAAUGUGUGUGAUGGGAUUCCCAGUGGUUACCCUAAUGCACCUGGAGGACCUGCAAGCGCAGUCCACUCACUCAGCUUACAAUGUAGGACUGCUGGAAGUUGGAAAAUAAA